CUCUCCCCUCGUCCACCGCUGCCGCCUCCUUCUUCUGCCGCUCCUGGUGCUGCUUGUGUGCUCGUUUGGUGCGGACCUGGUACCUCUUUUGUGAAGCGGCAGCUGAGGAGACUCCGGCGCUCGCCAUGGCCGACGAAAAGCCCAAGGAAGGAGUCAAGACUGAGAACAACGAUCAUAUUAAUUUGAAGGUGGCGGGGCAGGAUGGUUCUGUGGUGCAGUUUAAGAUUAAGAGGCAUACACCACUUAGUAAACUAAUGAAAGCCUAUUGUGAACGACAGGGAUUGUCAAUGAGGCAGAUCAGAUUCCGAUUUGACGGGCAACCAAUCAAUGAAACAGACACACCUGCACAGUUGGAAAUGGAGGAUGAAGAUACAAUUGAUGUGUUCCAACAGCAGACGGGAGGUGUCUACUGAAAAGGGAACCUGCUUCUUUACUCCAGAACUCUGUUCUUUAAAGACCAAGAUUACAUUCUCAAUUAGAAAACUGCAAUUUGGUUCCACCACAUCCUGACUACUACCGUAUAGUUUUCUCUAUUCUUUCAUUUCCCCCUUCCCCAUUCCUUUAUUGUACAUAAAGUAACUGGUAUAUGUGCACAAGCAUAUUGCAUUUUUUUUUUUUUUAACUAAACAGCCAAUGGUAUGUUUUGAUUGACAUCAAGUGGAGACGGGAUGGGGAAAAAUACUGAUUCUGUGAAAAUACCCCCUUUCUCCAUUAGUGGCAUGCUCAUUCAGCUCUUAUCUUUAUAUUCCAGUAAGUUAUUUUGCUCUCACUGUUUUAACAAAAAAAAAAAACAACAACAUAAAAAUCCUUGCAUACCUUGUUCAAUUGGAGAAUUUUAAUGUUUUUCAUUUAUCAUUGUAAAACCAAGGACAAUUUUAUAACUUUUUUGUACGUAGCUGUUACAUGUAGGGCAAUCUGUCUUUAAGUAGGGAUAAAUUACUCUAAAACAAAAAAGAAUCCUAGAUAGUUUUCCCUUCAAGUCAAGCGUCUUGUUGUUUAAAUAAACUUCUUGUUUAAAAUGAGCUGUUUUCUUUAUUCUGAGAAAUAUUAAAUAGAAAAUUGAGGCUUAGAAAAAACAUAAAUAGGCCUGCUUAGAAGUAACAUUUCAAGAAGGAAAUAAAGCUACUUGGUGUUUCUGACAGACUGAUACUGAUGCCAAACAAAGAAUAACAGUUUUAUAAAUAUCACCUUGUUCCAAAAGUUUCUCUAGGUCCCAUGUUAAUAUGCAAGUAUACUAGCAGAAAAAUUGGGCCAUAGUAUCGUGGAUUUCCAGGUAUUUUCUGUAUAUUAAGUGAGGCACGGAGCAUAGGGUAUAGGGUAGCACAUGUGGCAAGGAAAAAGUUCUGAUUUUGCCUUUGUUGCUGAUAAAACACUGAACCAUUCUAGCCUGCACUUAUCAUAAGUAAAUACUCCCUAACCUAAAAUAAAGUUUUCGUUCCUUAUUCAAGGAUUUUUUUUUUGAGACGGAGUUUUCCUCUUGUUGCCCAGGCUGGAGUGUAGUGGUGCAAUUUCAGCUCACUGCAACCUCAGCCUCCUGAGUAGCUGGGGGGUCAUAGGUGCAUGCCACCACGCCCAGCUAAUUUUUUUUCUAUUUUUAGUCGAGACAGGGUUUUAUCACGUAUGCCAGGCUGGUCUCGAACUCCUGACCUUAGGUGAUCCACCCGCCUCAGCCUCCCAAAGUGCAGGGAUUACGGCAUGAGCCACCACGCCUGGCCUAUUCAAGAAUAUUGAGGGACAGAAAAUAUCUAUAUAUAUCCAUCCUCAGAACCUUAAAUAUACAGGUCACUACAGUCUUUAUUAUUUUAAUUUUUGUUUCUUAGGGUUUCUUUUGGUGGUGGUUUUUUGAGAUGGAGCAUCAUUCCGUCUCCCAGGCUGUAGUGCAGUGGCACAAUCUUGGCUCACUGCAAGCUCCGCCUCCCGGGUUCACGCCAUUCUCCUGCCUCAGCCUCCCGUCUUAGGUCUUUUUGAAAGAGGUUAUGCCUCUGUUGCCUAGUCUGGAGUGGUGCAAUGGUGUGAUCUUGGCUCACUGCAACCUCCACCUCCAGGUCUUAAGAGAUCCUCCCUGCUCAGCCUCGUGAGUAGCUAGAACCGCAGGUGCAUGCCACCACAGCUAAUUCUUGUAUUUUUUAUAGAGAGUGUUUCGCCAUAUUGUCCAGGCCGGGCUCAAACCCCUGAUCUUAAGUGAUCUAUCUGCCUUAGCCUCCCAAUGUGCUGGGUUUACAGGCGUGAGCCACUAUGCCCAGCCCCUUUUUAAUUUUUUAAAAAUGUUUAUUUUUGAGAUGGAGUUUCGCUCUUGUUGCCCCAACUGGAGACCAAUGACAUGAUCUCAGCUCACUGCAACCUCCGCCUCCCGGGUUCAACUGAUUCUCCUCCCUCAGCCUCCGGAAAAGCUGGGAUUACAAGCAUCUACCAUCAUACCUGGCUAAUUCUGUAUUUUUAGUAGAGAAGGGGUUUCUCUAUGUUGGUCAGGCUGGUCUCCACCUCCCGACCUCAGGUGAUCUGCCUGCCUUGGCCUCCCAAAGUGCUGAGAUUACAGGCUUGAGCCACUGUGCCCGGCCAAAUUUUUAUUAUUUUUAAAUUAGAGGUGGGGUCUCACCAUGUUGACCAGUUUGGUCUCGAACUUCUGGCCUCAGUCCCUUGUCUUGGCCUCCCAAAGUGUUGGGGUUUCAGGUGUUAGACCCCAUGCCCAACCACUACAGUUUUUGUUUUUGUUUUUGUUUUUUUUUCAGACGGAGUCUUGCUCUGUCGCCCAGGCUGGAGUGCAGUGGCGCAAUCUUGGCUCACGGCAAGCUCCACCUCCCGGGUUCACGCCAUUCUCCUGCCUCAGCCUCCCCAGUAGCUGGGACUAAAGGUGCCCGCCACCAUGCCCGGCUAAUUUUUUUGUAUUUUUAGUAGAGACAGGGCUUCACCAUGUUAGCCAGGCUGGUCUCAAACUCCUGACCUCAGUUCAUCCACCCGCCUUGGCCUUCCAAAGUGCUGGGAUUACAGGCAUGAUCCACUGCGCCCGGCCUCACUGCCAUUUUAUAGAUGAGAAAGCCAAGUUCCAGAAAAGUUGUGAAAUAGACGGUGACUAUAAAACUGGGACUAGAGAUAGUAUCCUAAUGCUUGUUGAUUGUUUUUGUCCAUACUGAUUGUCAACCUACCAAUAUAAUCUACCAUCAAGUCA